CCUUUUCGCGGCCGGGCCCCAGCAUGGCUGCCCCCACGGCUGAGGGCCUGGCAGCUGCUGCGCCCUCGCUUUCUUGACAUUCCCUGGCUUCUGUGCUCUCUUCCCCAGGCCACCCCAGCAGACAUGUUUGCCAAGGCCUUUCGGGUCAAGUCCAACACGGCCAUCAAGGGGUCGGACAGGAGAAAGCUUCGAGCUGAUGUGACAACUGCUUUCCCCACCCUUGGAACUGAUCAAGUCUCUGAGUUAGUACCUGGAAAGGAGGAGCUCAACAUUGUGAAGUUGUAUGCUCACAAAGGGGAUGCAGUGACUGUGUACGUGAGUGGUGGUAACCCCAUCCUCUUUGAACUGGAGAAAAAUCUGUAUCCAACAGUGUACACGCUGUGGUCCUAUCCUGAUCUUCUGCCAACCUUUACAACAUGGCCUCUGGUGCUCGAGAAACUGGUAGGGGGAGCAGAUUUGAUGCUGCCUGGACUGGUGAUGCCCCCUGCUGGUCUGCCUCAGGUACAGAAGGGCGACCUCUGUGCCAUUUCUUUGGUGGGGAACAGAGCCCCUGUAGCCAUUGGAGUUGCAGCCAUGUCCACAGCUGAGAUGCUCACGUCAGGCCUGAAGGGAAGGGGCUUCUCUGUGCUCCACACUUACCAGGACCACUUGUGGCGGUCUGGAAACAAGUCCUCUCCACCUUCCAUUGCUCCACUGGCCCUGGAUUCAGCAGAUCUCAGUGAAGAGAAGGGGUCUGUCCAGAUGGACUCCACCCUGCAGGGAGACAUGAGGCACAUGACCCUGGAGGGGGAAGAGGAGAAUGGGGAGGUUCACCAGGCACGUGAAGACAAGUCUCUCUCAGAAGCCCCAGAAGACACCAGCACCAGGGGCCUGAACCAAGACUCCACAGAUAGCAAAACGCUUCAAGAACAAAUGGAUGAGCUGUUACAGCAAUGCUUCUUACAUGCCUUGAAGUGCCGAGUCAAAAAGGCUGACCUCCCUUUACUCACCAGCACUUUCCUUGGCAGCCACAUGUUCUCCUGCUGCCCCGAAGGACGACAACUGGACAUAAAGAAGUCAAGCUACAAAAAGCUCUCUAAGUUCCUGCAGCAAAUGCAGCAGGAGCAGAUUAUACAGGUGAAGGAGCUGAGCAAAGGGGUGGAGAGCAUUGUGGCUGUGGACUGGAAACACCCGAGGAUUACAUCUUUCGUCAUACCCGAGCCCUCCCCGACCUCCCAGACUAUCCAGGAGGGUAGCAGGGAACAGCCCUAUCACCCUCCAGAUAUAAAACCCCUCUACUGUGUCCCAGCCAGCAUGACCCUGCUCUUCCAGGAGUCUGGCCACAAGAAGGGGAGCUUUCUGGAGGGCAGUGAGGUCCGAACGAUCGUCAUUAACUACGCCAAGAAAAAUGACCUGGUUGAUGCAGACAACAAAAAUCUUGUGAGAUUGGAUCCCAUCCUAUGUGACUGCAUCUUAGAGAAAAAUGAACAGCAUACAGUCAUGAAGCUUCCAUGGGACAGUCUUCUGACCAGGUGUUUGGAAAAAUUACAGCCUGCCUAUCAAGUGACCCUUCCCGGACAAGAGCCCAUUGUGAAGAAAGGGAGAAUCUGUCCAAUUGACAUCACCCUAGCACAAAGAGCGUCUAAUAAAAAGGUGACCGUGGUCCGGAACUUGGAGGCCUAUGGUCUGGACCCAUACUCAGUGGCUGCCAUCCUUCAGCAGCGAUGCCAGGCUAGCACCACCGUCAAUCCUGCCCCUGGGGCCAAGGACAGCCUUCAGGUGCAGAUCCAGGGAAACCAGGUCCACCACCUCGGCUGGCUAUUGCUUGAUAACAAAACUGAGGCUGAGUUUAAGAAACAUGCCUGUGGUCCCCUGCUAGUAAGAAGCUAAGUAGGAACUGGAAUCAAAUCCAUCUAAGGCCCAUGCUCUUCUCAAUUCACCAUGUAGCCACCAUGGGACGGCAUCUUUUGCUGAAGGGGCCGGCCUGCCACACCCAUAAUGAUCACUGAAACUCUGUGCUGCGGGGCUGGGAUGAGCAGCUGUUAAACCAAAGCCUGUAAGUUACCUGAUCUGUGAAAUGUUCAUCUAAGAUGAGUCUAAGCAGCGGGUCAGGCCCCAGAGGCACCAUGUCACCUGUGAAGGUGGGAAGGAAGGACUUCUAACUCAAGUGAGAUGCAGCCACCAGGAUGCAGGGCCCAGCCUUCUCCUGUGUGCCUUCCCAGGUCUCUGGAACUGAACCUUGAUUCUGUUGCAGACCACCCAAGGGCAAGCAGCUCUGGCCAUCUCCCACUUGCCGGAGGUGAGUAGCAAGUAGUGUGAGCCUCACAGACUCUCUUCAUUCACUGUCAGUCCAUUAACCCGGGGACUCUCACAGUGAAGCCUCUCAUUUUCCUCAUCCCUUCCCUUGGGUAGCUCCCAGAGCUCCCCAUCCUCAGUCCUUGCCAGCUGAGCACAUGUCUAUGGGACCAGAUGUGCCUGACCCUGGCCCUACCCCUAUACCUUCCCGCUGGGAGCUUCUAAUUAGAAAGACCCCGUUGUCUGGUUACUAUUAUACACUCACUCUGUCUCUGACGCAUGUAGGCUAUUGCUCCUCAGGAGGUAAUAGCUUUCUCAUACUUGUCUAUAAAAAAUAAGUAAUGGAAAGAAAAUUCUAGAAGCUUCGGAAAGAUCUCCUCUCAUAGUUUCCAAUCAAGCUAGAGCCAUUUCCCCGUAAGAAAAGGCAGCUGUGCUGUGGCUUUCAAAGGCUUGAUUUUGAAUACAGUGAGAAGCAAAGCUGCCUUAGCCUAGGGUUUCUUCUUCCUGUUCCCCUUUCUUCAGCAGAUAGACCCAUCUAUCUCUCCCCUUCCCACCACAAACGCGGGGAAGUGACGCAAGUGGCCACAGGCACCUCUGCCUUCCAGGGCUGACUCAAAAGACAGCAGCCCUGACCUCACCAUUCUGAGGCCUGGCCCUCUGGCUGGUGAUGGGAAGCCCUGUCUGGGAGUGCCAGGAGCCCCGUGUGUAGCCAACACUACGAAUGUCACAGCCAUGGAAUGCCAGCACCCAGGUCUGGGAUGGCUGCUGCCCACAAAAAUAUCUGGCAGACAAGAUGUGACCCAUGGACCAAAUGAAUCACCUCCUGAAUUAGGCCAGCCAGCCACAGCCACGAGGGCUCACGGAUCCUUUUUCCACCCAAGAGAUGGCGUAUAAUCCAGACCAGUGGUUCUUAAACUUGUCUGCACAGUGCAAUCAUCUGGGGGAUCUUUAGAAACUUAGCUGCCUGGGCUUCAUCCCUGGAGAUUCUGAUUUAAUUGGUCUGGGGUGCAGUCUGGGCAUGGGAAUUUUAAAAAUCUCCUAGUUGAUUUUAAUUCGCAGCAACAUUCGAAAAGAACUGAAAUAGACAGACCCCUCACAACAAUUCCAGACCUCAAGGGUCUUCAUCCAGCUGCUGAAUUAACACUUGGUGCCAAGAAACACACAAACACCCCAAAGGUUUACCUAACAGGCACUAUCUGCCAUGAGAGCGAGAUCGAUACUAUAGCAAUCUUCAGAGGAUAAGACAAAGACUCUGAUUCCUAUUCACCUGCCAGAUUCUUAAGGAUCUGUCCACGGGUACAAAGCGAGAAACCAAGCAGACAGUUUUGCCUCUUGGGGUGGCCCAAGAUAGAGACAGAAUAGGGAACUCUGUUAUGAUUUAACAAAUAUAGACAUUGGCAUGUGAGGUGUCUCUCCUGGGGGCUCACACAUCUCAGUGCAUCUGGCAUGGAAUUCAUCUAUUCCGAUUAAGCCCCUGGCAUUGGUGGCAGAUGGCUGAGCUGUUCCCAAUGCACUUGGCAUGUCCAGGGCACUGGUGAAAAACAGGUUUGUGCUCACAUGUCCUAUGCGGUGGAAAAGGGCAAUGUCUUCUUUUAGCUCUGGAGGUGAUUGGGGAACAGCCAUGUAAAGAGGCUGGGUGCUAGGGGUUCACAGCGACACCCCGACCCUGAGUGAUUCUCUAAUGCUUCCAUUUAAAUAUUCUUAACAAAAUAAGGAGGACCAUACCCCUUUCGUCUGGGGCCUAACUCAGGGCAGAUUUGCCCUAAGCUGUUUUUCUUUAUUUUAUCACUAAAGCAACAGCAACAAAACCCUACUUCUGCACUCUAAUCAAUGACAUAUGUAAUCUUAAUUUUGGUGACUGGAGAGUGACCUAAUGCCCUAAGGAGAGGCUCUGAGUGAGUCACGUGGCUUCUGGUAUUCCCAGGUGGGCCCAGGGCACCCAGGAAUGCUGUGGCAAUGAGAGGGGGUCCCCAGGAUGAGGGUGGGCUGAGGAGGACGUGUGUCCCACCGGCAGUACUGCAGCUAUUAUAUACAUCCGUGCCUACUUUUUCUUGACCAAAAUCACAAACCUAAUUUUUGCUAAAAAAUUCACUCUCACUCUUUUUAAAUUUGUCAGUCUUUCCUCCUUCUGGCCCACGAUUUGAAUCAUCUCACACCUGUUUGCCCAUCAGAAGUCACUUUAUUUGUCAAGCUCUUCCUGAUCACUCCAGCCCUGAAUGAUGACGAUGAUUCACUACAGCUAAUAUGUACCGUGCACUAUUCUACUCACUUAGCAUGUAUUAGCUCAUUUCAUCAUCACAGCAAAUGUGUCACAAAAAAUACUAUUAUGAUGCUCAUUUUACAGUCAAGGAAAGUGAGCCACAGGAAGGUUAAAGCUAACCUACAUCUAAAGGCAACACUAUACUAUCUGGCACUUAAGUAAGCAUCUACUUACACACACACACACACACACACACACACACUUUUUUUUUUUGAGAUGUCUCCCUCUGUCACCCAGUCGAGAGUGCACUGGUGCAAUCACAACUCACUGCAGCCUCGACCUCCUAGGCUCAAGCAAUCCUCCUGCCUCAGCCUCCCAUGUAGCUGGGACUACAAGCAUGUGCCACACUCCUGGCUAAUUUUUUUUAUUUUUUUGUAGAAAUGAGGUGCCUUGCUAUGUUGCCCAGGCUGGUCUCAAACUCCUGGCCUCAAGCAAUACUCUCACUUCAGCCUCACGAAGUGCCAGGAUUACAGGUGUGACCCACCGCGCCUGGCUGCUUACAUUAACCUCCAAGUAGACUCAUCCAUCUCAGGUCUUCUUCCCAACUAGACUAAAGCUCUUUAAUGACUUACAUCAUACUUCAAUUUGUUCUCUGUGCCUGGUGCCUCUGAGCAUGAGGCAAAUAGGAAAUACUUGCUCAAGAACCUUCAAUGAUCCCCUAUUGCCUACAGUGGACAAAAAAGGUCUUAAUUUCUUCUAGGAAUUACAGUGCAGUGAGCCUUGGAUUUCCAUUUAGACUGAGUUCUGUGAGAGAAGCACCCACGCCUGUCUUGUCCUCUAUGGUGUCCCAGAUCCCAGUGCCAGCUUGACACAUAGUAGGGGUUAAGUACCUGCAGGAUGAACACAAGUGUGUGUUGGGCUUCUGACUCCCAUGACUAACUACAUGAUCUUGAGAAAGUCAGAUAAUCUCUAAGCCUCAGUUUCUUCAUCUAUACAUUUGGGAUAAAAAUCCCUUAUUGUCUCACAGGAUUGAUGUGAAGGUAAAAAUCAAAUGAGAUAAUGGGUACAAAAGUGUUCUGAAAAUCACCAAACCCAUUCAAAGGCAUGUAUGGUGACUAUCAUCCCAGGAAAGCAAAGUUCUACCCCUCUGAGCCAAUUUCAGUUUUCAUUUUCCUUGAGUCCUUCUUCUGAUUGGCCACAUGCCCAUAGAGUUUGUUAAUUCCUUUCUCUGCACCAGUGGUUGGCAAACUUUUUCUGUAAAGGGUCAGACAGUAAAUGUUAGGUUUUGCAGGCCACGCAGUCUGUUGCCACUAUUCAACUCUACUAUUGUGGCACAAAAGCAGCUACUGGAUGAGUGUGACUGGGUUCCAGUAAAACUAUUUAUGGGCCUGGCAUGGUGGCUCACACCUACAAUCCCAGCACUUUGAGAGGCCAAGGCAGGAUGAUCGCUUGAGCCCAGGAGUUCGAGACCAGUCUGGGCAACAUAGUGAGACCCUGUCUCUACAAAAAAAAAAAAAUACAAAAAUUAGCUGGGCACAGUGAAGUGCACCUGUAGUGCCAGCUACUCAGGAGGCUGAGGUGGGAGAAUGACCUGAGCCCCCAGGAGUUCAAGGCUGCAGUGAGCCGUGAUUGUGCCACUGCACUCCAGCCUAGGUGACAGAGCAAGACCCUGUCUCAAAAACAAAACAAACUUUAUUUAUGGAACCUGGCCAUGUGCAGUAGUUUGCUCUAUGCUGUUGUUUGUGCAGAGUCUCCUGCCUAGAACACUAUUAGCCCUAGUUCCACCUUCUCUAUGUAGUUUCCCAAUGCAAUUUCUCCAGUCUAUAGCCAUCUCUCCAUCCUCUGCUCUCUUAAUGUACCAGAUCCCUGGCAUUUUGAUUCCCACAUGGAGAAAGGUAAUCACAGUUUUGUCCUGGUCUCUCUUUCUCCUGAAUCAUACUUCCUAUGUUUCCUGUGUAUUUCCUCACACCACCAGUUAAUGGGCCUUUGUAACUUCACUCUCAUUUCAUGGACACUUUUCACAAGAAGACAAAGGCUUGGGCACUUCCUUGGAUUUUGCUCACUUUACUCCAUUCUGCAAUGAGGAGGCAACAAAGCUGGCUGGGGUAGGGAUGGAGGUAGACAGCUAGGCUCACCCCCUGGUUCUGUGACUCGCUCCCAAACACCAGCCCCAUGGCCUCAAAGCCUCAGAUUCCCAUUGCAGCAAAAGUACAAAUUACCAUCGUCACAGAUCUCUGCAGCUGCUGGCUAAUGUUAAAUCCAUACUGCAAGAGCCUAUAGAGGUGAUUUCAGAGCCUGUGUGGCUACAGCUGGCAUCUAAUUAUAUGCUGCCUUUUAUUGUUUAAUGAUUGUUUCACAUGUUAAUCCCAUCUCCCCAGUGAGAUGCUCUCUGGAUGGAGGCAGACAUUAGUUUGGUGCCUAAGCUUUUUGGCACCCCGCUUGGCUGAAACCUGGGCCAAACUUUAAGUAGGUGUCAGAUAAAUACCUGUUGAUUGGGUGGCAGGGGAGGGCAAGACAGCCUGGGGAGUCUCAGGCCAGAGCCCACCCCAGACCCCUAGGUCCAGGAGCACCUCACACUCAGCUGCACCCUGAGGGUCUGAUACCAAGAACACACACCAGGCUUUGGACUUUGGCGUUAGCCGUGUGGCUCAGCUCUUGGCAGCUAGCUGAUGAGAACAAAUGCAAGACCAUCAAAUGACCUGUGACGUCUGGGGAGCUACUUCCCCUCUCAGGGCCUCAGUUUCCUUAUCUGUGAAAUCAUGAAGUGAUACUGGAGAAGCUCUAAGGGCCCCUUCGCAGGACUAAGAUUUUACACAUAAGAUAGGGUGGUGUUUUUUUCUCAUCAUUGCUUCCUCUUCUAUUUCAGAGAAUUGGGUGUGGAGAUGGGGGCCUCUUGGAGGCUAGCUAGCAUGGCUGAAUGGCAGCAGGAAUAACCAAUCUAAAGGAGCACAAAGAACAUUUCUAACCGCCACGACUUUACUUUUUCACUGCUCACCACUUUUCUCUAUUGUCAGCAAGACUCUAUCUUAGCCAAGCCCAAGCCGGUCUACGCAUUCUUAACACACACAACUCAAGAAAACAAAACAAAAAAUACCCCGGAAGCCAUUCACCAUGAGCCUUUGCCACAUUUCCUCUUUCUCAGCUCUUAGCAAAUCUGUCAGCAGCAAUUCUUUCACCCCUUGGAAGGAAGCCAUCUCCAGGCUUAAGUCAGGGAGGAAAGCCUCAGGCCCCUCCUACAGGAGAAUGUCCAUCUGCAGCUGCCUUCCACACCCCAAACACCCGGUGCUUCUGUUGUGCUUGCCCUAGAUGGGAACGUCUGCAGGCAAGGGGCAGACACCCAUCUAUCUGGGCUGGAUUUGAAAUACCCUGCUCAAUGUCCAAACCGCAUUCAAAGGUGAGGUUAGGAGUUCAAGACCAGCCUGGGCAACAUAAUGAAACCCUGUCUCUUCUAAAAAAAAAAACAAAAACAAAAACAAAAAAAUUAUCCGUGCGCCUGUAAUCCCAACUACUCGGGAGGCUAAGGCGGAAGAAUCGCUUGAACCUGGGAGGCAGAGGUUGCAUUGAGCCAAGAUUGCGCCACUGCACUCCAGCCUGGAUGACAGAGCGAGACUCCAUCUCAAAAAAAAAAAAAAAAAAAAAAAAGUCAUUGGUCCCUUUGUGAUGGUCUCAACCAAAUGAGAAAGAGGAAUCCCUAUGGGGCCUUACUGCAGGGCCCCCUCCCAGGUCUUCGAAGGCCUGUGUUCUGAAAUGGACUCCACAGACCCACCACAGCAGUGAAGGGGUUGAUUUCCACAGGUCCCUCUAUGGCACUGUCCAUUGUCCCAAAAUUAAAAGGGUUGGGAACUCCUUAACUGUGUUCCCUAAUAGGUUAUUUGCAGCAGAGCAGGGAAGGGGCUUUAUCAUGGAGCUUCUGCUCCAUGUGGAAUUUGAGCAGCUCUGGUAGGGUGUAUUAACAGAGCAGAGGGAAAAAAGAGGUGGCGGGUGGAGGUUGAGAAUGGAAAGAGACUCAAGUCUCCAAAGACAAAAACGUAGAGCAGAUGGUCAAUGUCAACAGUCCGCCAGUAGUAACUGAAUGAACUGCCUAUGGGUGAGGAUCGUGAAAGGCACCUUGAGAGAUGACGCAGAUGGGAUGUGACCCUGUCCUUGGGAGUCUGCAGGUGACCUGAGAAGGGAAGACAGAGAUGGAUGCGCUGUGGCACACCAGAGCAAGUACAGUGUGAUCUGGGACAAAAAGCCUCAAGCAGCACAGAUCAGGCCACUCCCGCAGACUCCUCAGGUUGCCAGCAUGCCCCAGAGUCUGGACACGGGGUCCCCUGCUCUUUGAGGUGACCAUCUCAGUCUCUGCACAGCUCAGCUAGAGUGGGUUAUACCAGGGAACAGUAGCUCCCUUACAGGGACCUAAGUUCAAGCCCCUGCAGAGCCUCAUUAUAAUAUUAAAAACCGACAGUAGUCAGGCACUGCCCUGAAGGGUUCAAGGUCCUGAUCUCAUUUAAUCCCCUAAAUAACAAGAAAGAUGCUGUUACUCUUCACCAUUAGACCAUGCUGCCUUGCACGCUGGGCCACAGGUGGCCUGUGCUGGCCAUGCCCUUGGUCUUCUGUGAACUUGAUCAAGUCCACCUCACUAAGACUCCGAUUUCUAUUUUGUUUUUUUAAGAGAUGGGGCUCUCACUAUAUUGCCCAGGCUGGUCUCAAACUCCUGGCCUCAAGUGAUCCUCCCGCUUUGGCCUCCCAAAAUGCUGGGAUUACAGGCGUGAGCCACUACGCCUGGCUACUUAUAUUAACUUCCAAGUAGACCAUCCAUCUCGGGUCUUCUUCCCAACUAGACUGAAGCUCUUUAAUGACUUACAUCCACUGCUACUACUUCUCUAUGCCUGGUGGCUCUGAACAUGAGGCAAAUAGGAAAUACUUGCUCAAUACUUGCUUCAGUGGUUCUUGAGGUCUUAAUUUCUCCUAGGAAUUACAGUGCAGUAGUGAGCCUUGGAUUUCCAUUUAUACUGAGUUCCGUGAGAGAAGCACCCGUGCCUGUCUUGCCCUCUAUGGCGUCCCAGAUCCCAGUGCCAGCUUGACACAUAGCAGAGAUUCAGUAAAUACCUGCAGGAUGAACAUGAGUGUGUAUUUGGCUUCUGACUCCUAUUACUCACUACAUGGUCUUGAGAAAGUCAGAAAAUCUAUAUGCCUCAGUUUCUUCAUCUAUAAAUUUGGGAUAAAAAUCCUUUAUUGCCUCACGGGAUUGAUGUGAAGGUAAAAAAUCAAGCAGUCCGCCCACCUCGGCCUCCAAAAGUGCUGGGAUUACAGGCAUGAGCCACCACACGGAGACUGAUUUCUUUGUGAAAUGCAGUUUAUACAUUUGUUGUGAAGAUGAAAUGAGAUCUCAGGCCUCAAAGUGCUUAGCACAAAGUACACAGUAAGCACUCCAUAAAUGUUAGCUAGUGCGUCAUCAUCCAAAUUAUCAUCAUCACCAUCAUCAUCAUGAUCAUGAUCAUCAUCAUCUUCAGUAGUCAUUUGUCCAAAUUUUUCCAUUAUCAUCUUCAGUAGUCAUUUGACCAAAGCUUGGUCAGUGGGGACCCAAUAUGGGACCUUGAUUCCCGAUAGGCCCUUCAGCCAAGGCCACAUUAUGACUUUCAUGGGUCCUAAGAACUUUUGUCUUUGGGGCCAAGGGCCCCUUCCUCCAUUAAAAAAAACCCACUGAAAAUUAUAUUCUAUGAUUGCAUCGGUAUAAAGACAAAUACAUCAAUAUCCUAUAUUAAAACACUUUCUUCAACCUAAAUGUUCAUUUUUUUUCUCAUGAUUUUAAAGAAAUUAAAACGUUUUUGUGGACCUCUAAAGUCGUGUGUGCCUGUGGCACGAUGCCUGCUGUGCCUCAUGGAGAAGUGACCAUACUUUCCAGCUGUUCAGUCCCAGGUAGGGCGACUGACUGUCCCAGUGUGCUGGGGCUGAGGGUUUUCUCGGGAUGCAGGGCUUUCAAUGCUAAAACCAGGACAGUCCGGGGGAACCAGUGCAUUUGGUUACCCUAGCCCCAGGUCUGGACAGACUCCCUUCCUCUCUGCUGCAUCCCAGGGGCACCAUGUGCUCUUCUGUAAAGCUGUGCCCAUGUACUCAAUUCUGGAGGUUUUUCUGAUAUCCACAGCCACUCCAAGGCCAGGCUGUGGCCUAGGACACAACUGUGUGGGCUAUCUCGGAAGAAGCUCCCUCAAGGCAGGGUCUUUGGCUUGUUCACUGAGGCGGCUCCCAGAACAGUGUCAGGCACACAAUAGGGGUUCAUUAAACAUUGGCUUCAUGCGUUGAAGAAAACACAAAGAAGCAGUAACACGCAUGCACCCUAAACCCCAAAAUAAAUGUAAGGUAAUUAAAAGGUUCCAGAAUUUUAUAAAGGUCUUGUAGGAUUGCUGGUCCAUGGACCCAUUUACUUCUGAGACUACUGAACACCAGAUGAGAAUUCUGUCCUCUGCUUCUGAAAAUAGAUGACCCAAAUCCUUUCCAUUUCUGUUCUCCCCUGCUCCAGGUCUUCAUGAAGCCCCCUUUUUAGCUCAGAGGUCUAAAGUUUGAACCAGACAGAAGAGGGUGACACUCAAUCUUCUGAGAUGGCCACAGGAAUUUUCCCUUGGGACAUCUUAUGCCCUCAGGAGUUUCUAGAAGGUCUUCCUUUGGGUGUUUUCCUCCUUGGAUUUCCAGCUAGGUCCCUGUCCCCUCACCCAGCCUCACCUAGGUCAGCGUCCUUUCAGUCUCCCUGAGCCCUUCAUCUGACCAUUCUGCCUGAAAAGUCCUCCCUUCUCUACAUCUGACAGAAUUGGCCUCCUGCCCCUGGAACUGACAGUGUCUUUUGGGAUACCCACUCUUAUCUAGAAUUAGUGGAUUUUCCAACAACAUCAGCAUAUGCCCAAUUAUUCCAGCAUUGCUUUGACUCUCUGUACGUUAGUGUUAGUGGUACAAGCCUGUGUCCCUCAUUAGACUAUGAGCACACCACAGUCAGUGACUGUACCUUUUCCAUCUUUGUAUUCCCAGACCACCCUGAACCAGAGUACUGCAGAGUUAAUUAAGGAUGGACGGUGGGUAGGUGAGUGAGUGGAUCCCAAUACCCCAUCCCAGGCCAACUCUCUCCUAAGCUCUCUCAGUUCUUUCAGGCCAAUUUAGAGAGUAUUCCUUUGCAAAUGAUAUAUGCCAUAAGGGAUUGAUAUGCAGAAUAUAUAAACUACCACAAUACAAAAAAAAAAACCUGAUGAAAAAAUAGACAAUGGACAUGAACAGAUAUUUCUCUAAAGAAGAUCUAUAUAUGAUCUACAAACACAUGAAAAAAUGCUCAAUAUCACUAAUCAUUAGGGCAAUGCAAAUCAAAACCACAGUGAGAUACCAUUUCAUGCAUAUCAGGAUGCUUAUUAAUAAAAACAAUAAACAAGAAAAUAACAAGCAUUGGCAUGGAUGCAGGGAAACUGCAGCCCUGUGCAUUGCUGGUGGGAUUGUAAAAUAAUGCAGUCACUGUGGAAAAUGGUAUGGUGAUCCUCAAAAAUUAAACAGAAUUACCAUGUGAUCCAGCAAUUACACUUCUGGGUAUACACCCAGAAGAUGUGAGAGCAAGGACUCAAAUAUCAGAAAACCAGUAUUUGAACACCCAGGUUUGCAGCGGCACGAUUCACAGUAGCCAAAAAAGGUGGAAGCAACCCAAGGGUCCAUUGAUGGAUGAAACCCAAGUGUCCACUGAUGGAUGAAUAAACAAAAAAUGUGUUGUGUCCAUACAAUGGAAUCUCAUUCAGCCUUGAAAGGGAAGGAAAUUCUGACACAUGCUAUCACGUGGAUGAACCUUGAAAACAUUAAGCUAAGUGAAAUAAGCCAGUCACAAAAGGAUUAAUACUGUGUGAUUCUACUUAUAUGAAGUUCCUAGAAUAGUCAAAUUAAUAGAGACAGAAAGUAGAAUGGUGGUUGCCAGGGGUGGGGGGAGGGGAAAAUAGUGAGUUACUGUUUAAUUGGUAGGGAGUUACUGUUUAAUUGGUAAGGAGUUUCAGUUGGGGAAAACAAAAGUUCUGGAAAUGGAUGGUCGUGAUGGUUGUACAACAAUGUGAGGUUAUACUUAACGUCACUGCACUAUGCACUUAAGAAUGGUACAUUUUGGCUGGGUGCAGUGGCUCACACCUGUAAUCCCAGAACUUAGGGAGGCCGAGGCAGGAAGAUCUCUUGAGGCCCAGAGUCUGAGACCAUCCUGACCAACAUGGUGAAACCCUGUUUCUACUAAAAAUACAAAAAAAUUAGCCAAGCGUGGUGGUCCAUGCCUGUAGUGCCAGCUACUCGGGAGGCUGAGGCAGGAGAAUCACUUGAACCUGGGAGGCAGAGGUUACAGUGAGCCAAUAUUGCACCACUACACUCCAGCCUGGGUGACAGAUUUGAGACUCUGUCUUGGGGAAAAAAAAAAAAAAAAAAAAAAAAAAGGUAAAUUUUAUGUUAUGUGUAUUUUACCACAAUAAAAAAUAAAAAGGGCAGGGGAAACCUGGAGGCCAUGUCACUGGCUGGUUUUAUCUGUUUCCCAUAGAGUUGGGAGCUUCCCUUACUUUCUGUAUUCCAAGCGAGGAGUCAAUGCCACAUCUAAGCAACUGGGCCUCCAUCACGCCAAGCCCUCCAAGACCAGGCUCUUUUCCUAGGACUAGGCCACUCUCCUGGGAUGCAAAAUGAACACAAAAAAUGACCUGGACAGCCCAGCCUAGCUCAAAGGAGCUGCUGCAGUCGUAGCGGGCAUGCCUGCUCAAAACCUCCCAGGGGACUGCCCAGAAAGGUCAGGGGCACAGAAGCCUGUGCUCAGAGAUCAGGAAGGGGCCUCAAGAUGAACUGGUCCACCUACCCACAUUCUAGAGCAAACUAAGUCAUGAGGAAUGAAAAAGAUAAAAUAUAUUACUUUGACAUAAUUUGAGAUGGCUGUCACAGGGCCAGCAGACUGAGGUGGCCCUGCAAAGCUGUCCUUUGUGGGGGAAAUUUGCAUCUGUAGAGAAUCUCCUUUAAUGCAGCCAAGGCUUCUUCCCUUGUCCAGAUCUAGGAGAGAUUAAUGGAGUCUGACAUCUUUAAAGAUCUGAAAGAAACAUUUGCCAUGUCUUCUCUCUGAGGGUUGCUACCUGUGAGGUUUCAUCUACAUAACAAGACCACCUUGGCUAGCCAAGCCUCCUCUUCUUCCCCUCCCAAAACCUGUGUUGCCACUAAAACCUGAUUUACCAACCAUAACCUAUUUGGGGCCAUGCUCUGAGCCCACAGUCUUUCUGUAACCUUAGGAUGUGUAUGGGCUUCUGUACCCCACUGGGGCUUGGGUCUUCAUUCUGAAGGCUCCCGCGAAUACACGUUAAAUAAAUGUGUGUGCCUUUUUGCCUGCUCAUCAA